CAGUGUAAAAAUCCAACAUGUACCUUCCAGCUGUCUACAACACAAGUGCAUGCUCGUCGGACAAGAGGUCACAGCUAAGGCAACAAUCCACAUGAGUUGGGAAGGGCUCAUUUCACCUGUCAAACACUGCUGCUCUCAUGUGGAAUGCACUGUGGCUUUUUGGUCAAGAUAAUUACCGUGGAAGAUCCUAGGUGGCAGCAAAUCCCAGGUGAACAGACUGAGCCGUGGAGGUGGCAUAAGGCAACCCUAGCCGAGGAGAAUUGAGCCAGGCCCACCAGGCCCAUGGGUAACUGGACUGCAGCGGUGACUGAGUUUGUUCUGCUGGGGUUUUCCCUGAGCAGGGAGGUGGAGCUGCUGCUCCUGGUGCUCCUGCUGCCCACGUUCCUGCUGACUCUUCUGGGGAACCUGCUCAUCAUCUCCACUGUGCUGUCCUGCUCCCGCCUCCACACCCCCAUGUACUUCUUCUUGUGCAACCUCUCUAUCCUGGACAUCCUCUUCACCUCAGUCAUCUCUCCAAAAGUGUUGGCCAACUUAGGAUCUAGGGAUAAAACCAUCUCCUUUGCCGGAUGUAUCACCCAGUGCUAUUUCUACUUUUUCUUGGGCACAGUUGAGUUCCUCCUGCUGACGGUCAUGUCCUAUGACCGUUAUGCCACCAUCUGCUGCCCCCUGCGGUACACCACCAUCAUGAGACCUUCUGUCUGCAUUGGGACCGUUGUAUUCUCUUGGGUGGGAGGCUUCCUGUCUGUGCUCUUUCCAACCAUCCUCAUCUCCCAGCUGCCCUUCUGUGGCUCCAAUAUCAUUAACCACUUCUUCUGUGACAGUGGACCCUUGCUGGCCCUGGCCUGUGCAGACACCACUGCCAUCGAGCUGAUGGAUUUUAUGCUUUCUUCCAUGGUCAUCCUCUGCUGCAUAGUCCUCGUGGCCUAUUCCUAUACGUACAUCAUCUUGACCAUAGUGCGCAUUCCUUCUGCAAGUGGAAGGAAGAAGGCCUUUAAUACCUGUGCUUCCCACCUGACCAUAGUCAUCAUUUCUAGUGGCAUCACUGUGUUUAUCUAUGUGACUCCCUCCCAGAAAGAAUAUCUGGAGAUCAACAAGAUCCCUUUGGUUCUGAGCAGUGUGGUGACUCCAUUCCUCAACCCCUUUAUAUAUACUCUGAGGAAUGACACAGUGCAGGGAGUCCUCAGGGAUGUGUGGGUCAGGGUUCGAGGAGUUUUUGAAAAGAGGAUGAGGGCAGUGCUGAGAAGCAGAUUAUCCUCCAACAAAGACCACCAAGGAAGGGCUUGCUCUUCUCCACCAUGUGUCUAUUCUGUAAAGCUCCAGUGUUAGAAAGAGAGGAGCUGCCUUAGUGAAAGAGUGAGCUAGCUAAGGAAUUCUGAAUAGUCUAUAGUGGAAAGACUGACUGCGGAGACAGAGACUUGAACGCUGGCCUUGGUUUUCACUUUAAUCUGUGACCGCAGCUGUGUCACCAGCCAUUCUGACUCUCAGUACUCUCAGCUGAAGUGCAACAGGGCUGGACUUGAUGAUCUCUAAGCCCCAUCCACACUGAAUAUUGUAAGAAUGGAAGGGCCAUGCAGCCUAUUUCCUCCUAAAGUCCUAACAUGUUUGGCCCCAUUUCUUUAUGGAUCCCGAACACAACUGUUCUAUCGGCUUGACACGAAGUCCUUCCUGAACUUCUCUGCACGGACCCUCUUUCUUUCCAUCCUCUGCAGGAUCUUUUUAGAAAUAACCUUCAUUAUUCUCUAAUCCACUAUCAUAUCCAUUUUUUUUUCGGGCAUUUGCAAUGAUUGUGUUGGGUGCAUGUCAUCUGUGUUAUUUAAUAAUAUUGCUUUCUGUAAUAGAACAUGUUCAUAAUAUCCAAUAUGCUCAUGUCGUUAUGUAAGACAUGGCCCUGUUCCCCUAGCCACUAAUGAUUGAUCCAUGGAUGGAUAAUCUGACUGAAGGCAUAACCCAUCACCUGCAGGGACACUUGCACACCUAAGAGACUGGCCAGUGACCUAUGACCUGUGUGGCUUGGCUGGACCAGAGGAGCUGUGUAAACAGAUACGACUUUUUUGAGAAAUUGAAGCAAAAAACACAGAGAUUAUUCCACACAAGUGUGAUGCUUCCCCUGGAAGCAGAAAUAGGCUUGGUGGCUGGAGUGGCCACUUUGGGUGCCAGGUGCAAGCUGAUGAAUAAUUAGAGGAAACCAGUCUGCCCCUCAGAGAGAAUGCAGUUGAUGUAUAGAGAAAAACAGAGAAGAGAGAGAUGACAGCCCACUCACAACACAAAGGCACAACACAAAGAGCCCUCUUCUCUCAUGACUUCCUAGGGCUGGAGCUGGUAGAAUUUUGAUUCCUAUUCCUGGAUUUGAUGUGUUUUGCCUGUACCUGUAAAUGAAAUCCCUUUUUAUUGAGCUAUCUUGAGAAGGUCUUAGAUUCUUGUGACCAAAAAGCAGCUUGACUACAAAGUUCAUUAUCUCUCCACAAGGCAUAGCUUCUCCCCUUUUCUGGCUCCAUACACCUGGAAAGAAUCUGUUUUGUUUUUGUUUUGAGACGGAGUCUCACUCUGUCGCCCAGGAUGGAGUGCAGUGGUGCAAUCUCAGCUCACUGCAACCUCCGCCUCCUGGGUUCAAGUGAUUCUUCUGCCUCAGCCUCCUGAGUAGCUGGGACCACAGGCGCGUGCCACCAUGCCUGGCUAAUUUUUGUAUUUUUAGUAGAGAUGGGGCUUCACUGUGUUAGCCAGGAUGGUCUCGAUCUCCUGAACUCGUGAUCUGCCCACAUCGGCCUCCCAAAGUGCUGGGAUUAGAGGCAUGAGCCACUGCGCCCAGCCAAGAAUCUGUUUUUAACUGCAUUCCUAGUCUGAAUUCUUGGUGCCCAAACACUGUCUGGGAUGCUUACUUGGACCCACUCUGGGCCUGUGGUUCAGCUCAGUGCAAACCAGCUUUUCAAUAUCAUCAGAAUCUCUGAGGUUUAAUUUCUUGUCUUGCUUGGCCGCCAGUGCUGCAGCAUCCACUUUGCUAAAUUAACCCCUAUGCUCUGCGUGGAACUGGUCAGAAGGACACAUGCAUACCUAAGGAACUGCUGCAGAGUUCUGUGGACAUAAAUGAAGACUACUUAAAUGAGCACAGAUGCCACUUAUUCAGAGCUAGCUAUAUCAGGGGAGUCAGCCACCAUCACUUGCAUUUGGCAGAGAGUCAAAGGCAGGCAGGGGAGUGGAAAGCUUCAUAGUAGAAAAAAAGGGAAAGGCCCGAGUAUUCCCUGACUGGAGGAUUUUGGCAUGGGGAAGCUGGAGGUGAGCUAACUAGUGUUGCGGGAAGUCAGGCACCCCAAACGGAGGGACCGGCUGAAGCCAUGGCAGAAGAAUGUGGAUAGUGAAGAUUUCAUGGACACUUAUCACUUCCCCAAUGAAUACCCUUGUGAUUUCCUAUGCCUGUCUUUAAUCUCUUAAUCCUGUCAGCUGAGGAAGAUGUAUGUCACCUCAGGACCAUGUGAUAAUUGUGUUAACUGCACAAAUUGUAGAGCAUGUGUGUUUGAACAAAUACGAAAUCUGGGCACCUUGGAAAAAGAACAGGAUAACAGCAAUUGUUCAGGGAAUAAGAGAGACAACCUUAAACUCUGACCGCUGGUGAGCCGGGGGGAACAGAGCCAUAUUUCUCUUCUUUCAAAAGCAAAUGGGAGGAAUAUCACUGAAUUCUUUUUCUCAGCAAGGAACAUCCCUGGGAAAGAGAGUACGCGCCUGGGAGUGUAGUCCUAUAGACGGCCCCCCUGGGCGUGCCCGUCUUUUAUGGUCUGUAGACUGUAGGGGUCAAAUAGACCCCAGUCUCCCAUAGCGCUCCCAGGCUUAUUAGGAAGAGGAAAUUUCCACCUAAUAAAUUUUGGUCAGACUGGUUGCUCUCAAAACCCUGUCUCCUGAUAAGAUGUUAUCAAUGACAAUGGUGCCCGAAACUUCAUUAGCAAUUUUAAUUUCACCCUGGUCCUGUGGUCCUGUGAUCUCGCCAUGCCUCCCUUUGCCUUGUGAUAUUCUAUUACUUUGUAAAGUACGUGACCUCUGUGACCCACACCUAUUCGUACACUCCCUCCCCUUUUGAAAGUCCCUAAUAAAAACUUGCUGGUUUUUGUGGCUUGGGGGGCAUCAUGGAACCUAGUGACAUGUGAUGUCUCCCCCGGCUGCCCAGCUUUAAAAUUUC